CUAGUCCUGCAGUAGGCGGCCCGGGGCCACACCGCGGCCGCCCAAGCCAGUGCAAGGCCCAGGGGCCUGACAUCGCUCCCAGCGCUCGAGGACCGAGGCCUGCUGUGGAGGACACCGUGCUCCCUCGGGACCUGCUCUGGAUUCCGGCCCGGACGUCCCCUUGGAGCUCUGCAUCUCCAACCUGGAACCCAACCCAGAAGUCUCAAGUUUGACGCAUCACGUGGCGUGCGGAUCCACUGAGGGUCCACAGAGAGGGGCGCCCAUCUCCUGCGUCUCAGUUAUCCUGGUAAUUGUGUAUCUGCCCAUUGUUCGUUGCCUCAUUAACUUGGCUUUCUAGGUGCACCCACCUUGCCACCAGAGAAGUCCAAAUCCUGACUUCUCUCCAAGGUGUUGGGAAUUCUGUGCCCUAAAGAAUUCCGACUCAGAUCCGAACGGGGAUCUGGUGGAAUCGAGGGUGAAAGACCAGAGGGACAAUGUUCUACUAUCCCAACGUGCUUCAGCGCCACACCGGCUGCUUUGCCACCAUCUGGCUGGCGGCGACUCGCGGCAGCCGGUUGGUGAAGCGCGAAUACCUGAGGGUGAAUGUGGUGAAAACCUGCGAGGAAAUCCUCAAUUACGUGCUGGUACGAGUGCAACCCCCGCAGCCCGGCCUGCCGCGGCCCCGCUUCUCCCUCUAUCUCUCAGCCCAACUUCAGAUCGGUGUGAUCCGCGUCUAUUCUCAACAAUGCCAGUACCUCGUGGAGGACAUCCAGCACAUCUUGGAGCGCCUCCACCGUGCCCAGCUGCAGAUCCGAAUAGAUAUGGAGACUGAGCUACCCAGCCUGCUGCUUCCUAACCACCUGGCCAUGAUGGAGACCCUAGAAGAUGCUCCAGAUCCCUUUUUUGGGAUGAUGUCUGUGGAUCCCAGACUUCCUAGUCCUUUCGAUAUCCCUCAGAUUCGACACCUCUUAGAGGCUGCAAUCCCAGAGAGAGUUGAAGAGAUCCCUCCUGAAGUUCCUACAGAGCCCAGGGAGCCAGAGAGGAUUCCGGUCACUGUGCUGCCACCUGAGGCCAUCACGAUCCUGGAGGCAGAGCCCAUACGGAUGCUGGAGAUUGAGGGUGAACGGGAGCUCCCAGAGGUCAGCCGCCGAGAACUGGACCUGCUGAUCGCAGAGGAAGAAGAAGCUAUCUUGUUAGAAAUCCCGCGGCUCCCACCUCCAGCUCCUGCAGAGGUGGAAGGAAUAGGAGAGGCACUGGGUCCUGAGGAGCUGAGGCUGACAGGCUGGGAACCUGGGGCCCUACUCAUGGAGGUGACCCCCCCGGAGGAGCUGCGUCUGCCAGCCCCACCCAGCCCAGAGAGGAGGCCCCCAGUCCCCCCACCUCCUCGCCGCCGCCGUCGUCGCCGGUUACUGUUCUGGGACAAGGAGACUCAGAUCUCCCCGGAGAAAUUCCAGGAACAACUGCAAACCAGAGCCCACUGCUGGGAAUGUCCUAUGGUGCAGCCGCCCGAGAGGACCAUCAGAGGCCCUGCGGAGUUGUUCAGAACCCCAACUCUCUCUGGCUGGCUACCCCCUGAACUACUGGGUCUCUGGACCCAUUGUGCCCAGCCACCCCCAAAAGCCCUCAGGCGAGAGCUGCCUGAGGAGGCAGCCGCUGAGGAGGAAAGGAGAAAGAUUGAAGUUCCAAGUGAGAUUGAGGUCCCGAGGGAGGCCCUGGAGCCCAGUGUUCCCCUUAUGGUGUCUUUAGAGAUCUCCCUAGAGGCAGCUGAAGAGGAGAAGUCCCGCAUCAGCCUCAUCCCACCAGAAGAACGGUGGGCCUGGCCUGAGGUGGAGGCGCCAGAAGCUCCUGCAUUGCCCGUGGUGCCUGAACUCCCUGAGGUGCCCAUGGAGAUGCCUUUGGUGCUGCCCCCAGAGCUCGAGCUGCUCUCACUGGAAGCAGUGCACAGGGCAGUGGCACUGGAGCUGCAGGCUAACAGGGAGCCCGACUUCAGCAGCCUGGUGUCACCUCUCAGCCCCCGCAGGAUGGCUGCCCGGGUCUUCUACCUGCUCCUGGGUGAGUGUAUGCAUGUGUGUGUGUGUAUGUGGGGCAGGGACACAGAGACCAGAGGCCCGUACAGGGACUCCCCCGACCUGCCCUCUCCUCGCCUCUUGACCAGUGCUCUCAGCGCAACAGAUUCUUCACGUGAAACAAGAAAAGCCAUAUGGUCGCCUCCUGAUCCAGCCGGGGCCCAGAUUCCACUGAGGUUAGAGUCCAUUUACAAAGCUGCCAGGAAACCGGCCACUUCUAGUAAACCACGUCGUGCCUCACUGGGUCCUGCUUACCUCAUUUCUGAAUGUGCAUUUCCAGCCUUCUUGCUCUCAGAGCUAUUGUUCAAGCAGAAAACAAGCUGCUUUUAUUACAGUAUGAUGUCAUGACUCAUUUGUAACAGAUCCAGCCUCAGGGACAGCCCUGUAAGGCAGCAAGUGGGGCUGGCUCCAAAUGGGUAUGAGUCUCAGAAUCUUUGGUAAGGCAGAACUGAACUGGGCUGAGAGGUGGUCUUAAGGCCUGGGCAGGCUCUAUUCUCUCUGGACUGGCUGCAGCCUGCAGUCUAGGAGAGGCCCAGUACAGCCUGGAGCUCCUGAGCCUUGUCAACAGGCAGUGAGCCCAGAGCUGCUUGAAAGCUGUCGGUGUGCUGUUUGGCCAGGAACGUCAGGAGCAGCAACAGUGCGGCCUUGGUGUCUGGGUGGAGAGGGAGGGAGAAAGGUCGGGGCUCCUAAAGCCUCGCUGCCCCAGGCUCUCUGAGCCCUGCCACUCCCAGCCUCCCGCAAGCCCCUGCCUAUGACUCCUACCCUCACCUGGUGGGAUCUUGUUGUCAGCCAGAAUGAGGCUGCAGAUACGCAGAAGCUCGGGAGCCACAUCUAUAACCUGUGAGGAAAGAGUGGCUGACUCAGGGCAGCAGCCCCAGACCCCAGGUCUAGGAGGGUGGUCAGGACCAAGGAGUGGCAGAAUCUCUUAUCAGGGGGGUGGUUGCACCUGGUACUGAUUCACAGGCAUCCAAGACAACUAUGAACAUGAGAAGAACCAAUGAAA